AUCACAUCAGUGGCCCUUGGAGGAGGGAGCGCAUCGCCCGAGGUGACUGGAGUGGGGGCGCCCCUGGCAGUGAGCGCGGGGACGCGGGGGAGGUCCCGAUAGCGGGUUUCCUGAGCUAGGGCCAGUGAGGGCACCGGGGUAUUUGCAGGCGUUCCCGCAGGCCAGGAGGGAGAGGGCUCCAGGGCUCGGCUUCCCUGGGGCGGGGAAUCCCUUGCCCUGUCCCGAGGCGCAGGGGCGGGGCCGGGGGGCGCCCCUGACGCGGCGGCUGAGGUGUUCCCAGCCCGGUGUCGUUCCCCGCGGUAGGUGGUCCCCGACGAGCUGCAGCCAUGGGAAACACCACCAGCGACCGGGUGUCCGGGGAGCGCCACGGCGCCAAGGCUGCACGCUCCGAGGGCGCAGGCGGCCAUGCCCCGGGGAAGGAGCACAAGAUCAUGGUGGGGAGUACGGACGACCCCAGCGUGUUCAGCCUCCCUGACUCCAAGCUCCCUGGGGACAAAGAGUUUGUAUCAUGGCAGCAGGAUUUGGAGGACUCCGUAAAGCCCACACAGCAGGCCCGGCCCACUGUUAUCCGCUGGUCUGAAGGAGGCAAGGAGGUCUUCAUCUCUGGGUCCUUCAACAAUUGGAGCACCAAGAUUCCACUGAUUAAGAGCCAUAAUGACUUUGUUGCCAUCCUGGACCUCCCUGAGGGAGAGCACCAAUACAAGUUCUUUGUGGAUGGACAGUGGGUUCAUGAUCCAUCAGAGCCUGUGGUUACCAGUCAGCUUGGCACAAUUAACAAUUUGAUCCAUGUCAAGAAAUCUGAUUUUGAGGUGUUCGAUGCUUUAAAGUUAGAUUCUAUGGAAAGUUCUGAGACAUCUUGUAGAGACCUUUCCAGCUCACCCCCAGGGCCUUAUGGUCAAGAAAUGUAUGCGUUUCGAUCUGAGGAAAGAUUCAAAUCCCCACCCAUCCUUCCUCCUCAUCUACUUCAAGUUAUUCUUAACAAAGACACUAAUAUUUCUUGUGACCCAGCCUUACUCCCUGAGCCCAACCAUGUUAUGCUGAACCAUCUCUAUGCAUUGUCCAUUAAGAUAAAGAAACUAAGGCUCAGAGAAGGUCAAAUUGCCAGACAGUGUGAUGGUCCUUAGCGCAACCCAUCGCUACAAGAAGAAGUAUGUUACUACUCUGCUAUACAAGCCCAUUUGAAGGGAUCCCUUCUUGCCUCUAAGGAUUCAGGAGAAGCAUCUCCCUUGCAUUUCUGGACUGAACCAGUCUUACCUGAGACUGGAAGGCUGAUUUGCUUUGAGGCUGAUAUGUGUGUUUCAGAGCCUCUGAGUAGGAUGCUCUGCUUUUGCAUUUGAUUGCAGAUGAGAGCUUUAUGAGUUCACGGAAUUUAUUUUAAGAAAAAAAAAUAUACAUAUGAGAAGAAGGUAAAUGGAAGCCUCCUAGCCCCAGCUAGAAGUAUUGUUUCUGCCUGUGGGUUUUCACCAAGACCUGUUUGGGGGCGCUGCAGGAAUAACUAUAUAGGAAGAUUUUUCCUAAAAUGAAAGAACAGCAAACUCUUAGGAUCCUUGUUGGGUGGAGAUUCUAUCACUGCUACCUUGGCUCUCCAAGGAAUGGGCUUGUGCUAGACCGCUGCCCUACUUAACAGCUGCCUCAUUGCAAGGGCAGUUUUUCUUGCAUGGGUUCUCUAUAUUCCCAGAGUAUGUGGCACAAUCUGUGUUGUUUAUAUGAUACCAGAUGCCCCACAAGAACCCUUAUUCCUCUCAUUUCACAUUCUUCCUUUAAUAGCCUCCUUCAGAUCCCAUACCUGACCCCUCUCUAACACAAAACUUAUUGGGUAAGUGACUUUGAAAAGUUUUGUGGCACCUGACCCACCCCAGACACUAGGGCUAUCAGAAGGUCUCCUUUUUAGCCCAGCACAGGCCCAGGCCACUUUGUCGUGUUUGUUUUAACUUCUAAAGAAAAUAUGUUUCAGCAUUAUAAGAAAGGCAGAAUGCAGAACACCUACAUUUUUGUUUUAGUUUGGUGCCAAGGCUCAGGCUGUAUUGGCAAAUUCCCGAAAGUUUUCCCACUUUGCCUGGCCCUGCUUCUGUCUUUUCUUUCUCAGUAAACAGUUCUGAAGGCAGGAGUGGAACCCGGGAGUAUUUUCAUGUCUUUCAUCCUUGAAAGAUUUUUAUGUGCCUGCAUUUUUUUUUUAAUUAAAAAAUGCCUUUUCAUUGGUCUUAAGAGACCGCAUUGGAGAAUUUCAGGCUUUUGAUAAAUGCUUCUUCAAAGAGAUUUUCUUCUCUAGUCUAGCCUUCCACAUUCUUAGAUUAAUAUGGCCAACCCUGUACACAUCACUACACUAAACACUGCUCUAGAUAAACUGCUCAAGUUCAUUUAACUCAUUUGAUGCACCUAAAGGGGUUCCUCAUUUUAAAGAUUUGUUAGGCCAAGAAGCAAGAGAGUAUUCCUAGUAUUCCCAACCAUGAAAAGUAUCAUUCUUUGCACCAAAUGUUAACAAAAUCAUUUUGUUCUCCUGCCUCUUCUUUUUAAAGGUGUUUGAUGAUUAAGUGGGGUCACUGAAUUCCAUUUGUGGACUGAAAAGUAUUCAAUCCACUUUUGGGGUUCAGAGAUAAAACAUUUUUUCCCAAGUAGCUGGGGCUCUUCCAUUUUGCAGAUAAGUCAAAUAAUCAACACUAAAGGAGGCUAAACUGUUGAUGAAUGAGAGACUCCCUGACUGCUCAGAUGACCCUAGCCACACUGAAAGGGCACCUACAGGUCAGUUUAGCUACCUCCUGUCUUUCCCAUGCAAAGCUGAUAACACAGUUGUCUUUGGACUUGUAGACCUCUUGGAUUCCAGGUGUGAUGGAGUAAAGUGUGGGAUUGUUGUUUUGCUGGGAUGCAAAUAACUAAAUGCUUUGGUGGUUAAUUGCUAAGAGUAAAUACUACUUUAGCCAUCCAAGGCCACCUUCUGCAGCAAAAGGCUUUUGUGGAGAACCUUUUAUGUUCCCAACCACUUUUUGAAUGGUGUGCCAUUUAAAAAUCCAGGCCAGAUCCUAUUAUAACCAACUCUCAGGAUUUACAGCCUUCAGUUGUACUAGAAUUUUGUUUUUAUCCAAUACUCAUUAAAUAAGUGGGCCACUUAGGAAGAUUCAAAAUCUUGGUUAUUACAUGAAGUUUGUUAUAUUUCUUGUCAACAGUAUUGAAAUGUAAUAUGUAUGUGUUCAUGUAUGAAAAUUUUUACUCCACACAGGUGUUUCAGUAGAGUGGGGCAGGAAAAGAGAUCUCUUCGAUUUCUUUCAGGCCUGAGGCUUUUGUGAAAUGCGUCAGCCCCCUGUGACAGUAGGUUUUGAUGCUAGUGAUCUUCAGAUCUUUCUCUCUGGAAAUGUGCAGAGAGUGUCAGUUUCCCAAGUUCUGAGGUAACUCUCAGCCCAGAUGUGAAAUGGGAGCCUACCAGCUGGUAUAGAAGGGAAUGGGUAGGAGGCACUGGGUGCUGACUCAUUCAGCACUGUCCCUUUUCUAUACUGCUGAUACAUCCCAUGGUUCUGAGAAGCCUUAUCUCAGUCUAUUUGGAAGAGAGGGAGGAAGAGAAGGAAGUAACCCAAAGUACUACUCAUUUAUCAUUGUAUAUUGAUUAGUUAAAGGGAUAAUUAAUUUAAUGCUGAGGAGAGUUUGACAGAUUUUGAAAAUGAGUAAAGGCAAAAAAAAUUUUUUUAGCCUUUAUUUUGCUUUUGGGAAUUUUACAGAGUCAAAGUAGGCAGAAUAAGAAAAUAGUUCUUCAGGAGGGCCGACCUUUAAAGAACUUCAACAUAGUUUCGGAAUUGUGGGGAAGAGAAGAGUGACUGAGCUGAGAAGUAAUAAUAGAAUAAAGGGUUGAGUAACUUACAACUGAAAAUGAUCUCUUUUAAAAAGAAAUUAAAUCAGACACCACAUGGUGGUGUCCUUGGAUCUCACUGUACAGAAUUAGCAGUGUAUAACCAUCUUCUCUUUUCAUCUUGUUCCAAUUCUCUCCUCUUUCCUUUCCAUUCUGCUUUAAGCUCAUGUGUCAGGCAGACUUUACCAGAGUGUCAGACAUUACCUAAAACACAUACGUUAGCCAUGCUGCUGGUAUGGAGAAAUUCCACACCAUGAUUAUUAGCCUCCUUUAAGCUGAAUGGGAUUUAACCAUUCUAGGCAACACCCCUGAAGGGCAUACCUAACCUCAAUAGUGUUGGCUUUUAAAACGUAUGUUUGUAUGGUAGAGAAACUUUGUAAAAGAAGAAUCCAAGAGAAGUUUGUGAGGAUCCUACAAACCCAGGCCCACUCACUUUGCUCUAAUUCUUUCUAGUAUCUUGUAGAUCUAAUGGGUCUGGGAUAAAAACUUUGAAAAGUGUCAAUAUUCCAUGUAUGCUGCUGAAAUGAAGUUAAGUUUGGAAAGAAGUGAUACCUCUAGACUGGGUUUAUAUUAAUCUGGGAUAUAAAUGAAGAAGACAUACUAAUAGAACUCCUUGCUUUUAAUUGGGGAAAUAGGGCUUUAAUAAUUUUGACCUCAACUAAAAAUGAUAUGCAAUAGUCUCUGUGUGUGUUUGAAAUACAUUGUGUUCUCAGAGAUUUCUACAUUCUCACGUUCUAGUGAUUUGGGGCAUGGGCUUAAUAGCAGAUGUACAGUGUAUUCCUGCAUUAUUGUGAUUCCCCUUAAAGCCCAGUUCUUGCUGUCUUCUACCAGGGGCUGCUGACUCCAGUUACCCAUGGAAUGCAGGACCUGGGAGGGGUAGCCAUUAGGGUCUUUCAAAACUCUUUGGAUCUAAGCAUUUGUCUCUCCUUAAGUGCCAAUCACAAUUGGAUAUGGAAGGACUGUGAUUUCUGCAAUGAACCCAAACUUUUAGAGUAAAAAGCCAAAUUUAAAUUAUAAGAAAGAAGGGAAAAAAGAGAAAAACUCAAGUCUAUUACUUGUAGAGUCCAAUUCUUAGCAAUGGAAUCGCUCUAGGAUUCUAGUUUGGGCUUUGUCUGGAUUUGCUUUUCUCAGUUGUGCUUUGAAGUGAAUAAGCUUUGUUACAAAUUAAUUUUUUAUUAGUUCCAAUAUUAGUUGGAGUUAACUUGAAUUGAUUGUAUGUAGCACAGCACUUUUGCAGUAAGAUUGGUGUGAAAUACUAAACACUAUGGAUUUUGUAGGUGUCAGGUUAAAUGGUCAAGGGAUACCUACAUUAAGUCAUAUAUUAGGUAUUGAUGAUCUUACUUCUUUUCUGUUCCCCUGUACAAAACACUUACCUAACCCAGCUUGUGGUUUUAGGACAGCCAAAGCUCACUGUUGUUGGUUAGUCCUAAUCACUACACGGGUCUCAUAAAUGAGACUUGUUUGAAUUUUGGUACAUUGGAGCAUGUUGGUUGGUAUUACACGGCAGCAUUUCGAAUGAGUGCAGCUCUGUGUCUGUCAGAAAGGAGAGAUAAGACUACUUUGAAGGGAAUUAAAUAUGUGAGUCCUCUUUUUAAUGGUGCUUUUUGUAACCUUUAAUGCUGAGGUACAGAGCUGCUUUUCAAUAUUUCAUAAAGGAGUGGCAGACAAGAGUGGAUUUUAAAGCUGUUCUUCAAACGUAAUUUGUCACUGGACUCUGACACACCUGGAAAUUAUAUGAUAUGAUACAUACAGAAAUGUUGUGGGUUUUUUCCAUAAAACUUUAAUAAAAGUAUUAUACAGCAAUAA